AGCAGUGUUGGUUUCUCUUCUUGACUUGAUGCAGGCACAGAUUUAUCAAGCUCCUCAGUCAACAAACACAUCACCGGAAGAAAUAUGGAAGGAAAGGAAUUUUAAAAGGAAAUACCAAUCUCUGUGCAAACAAAGCCUUGUAUAUUCAUGUUUGCACCAAUCUACUGUGAGAUUUAUGAAGAAAAACAAAUUGCGGACAACUCUCUAUGUACACUUACAAAUGCCUCAGUUGAUGCUUGUGGGCUGUUUGUCAGCGUUCUGUGAUAAUGAACACAUGGACUUCUGUUUAUUAAAUUCAGUUGACCCCUUUAGCCAAUUGCCAGGAGCCUGGAUUUUUACUUCCAACUGCUGAUAUCUGUGUAAAAAUUGAUCUACAUCCACCCUUUAAAAGCAUUGAUGAAUUAAUUAGAACUUUAGACAACAAAGAAAAAUUGAAAAAGAAUUCUCAGUAAAAGCGAAUUCGAUGUUCAAAACAAACUACAAAGAGACAAGACUUCUCUGUUUACUUUCUAAGAACUAAUAUAAUUGCUACCUUAAAAAGGAAAAAAUGAACAGCACAUGUAUUGAAGAACAGCAUGACCUGGAUCACUAUUUGUUUCCCAUUGUUUACAUCUUUGUGAUUAUAGUCAGCAUUCCAGCCAAUAUUGGAUCUCUGUGUGUGUCUUUCCUGCAAGCAAAGAAGGAAAGUGAACUAGGAAUUUACCUCUUCAGUUUGUCACUAUCAGAUUUACUCUAUGCAUUAACUCUCCCUUUAUGGAUUGAUUAUACCUGGAAUAAAGACAACUGGACUUUCUCUCCUGCCUUGUGCAAAGGGAGUGCUUUUCUCAUGUACAUGAAUUUUUACAGCAGCACAGCAUUCCUCACCUGCAUUGCCGUUGAUCGGUAUUUGGCUGUUGUCUACCCUUUGAAGUUUUUUUUCCUAAGGACAAGAAGAUUUGCACUCAUGGUCAGCCUGUCCAUCUGGAUAUUGGAAACCAUCUUCAAUGCUGUCAUGUUGUGGGAAGAUGAAACAGUUGUUGAAUAUUGCGAUGCCGAAAAGUCUAAUUUUACUUUAUGCUAUGACAAAUACCCUUUAGAGAAAUGGCAAAUCAACCUCAACUUGUUCAGGACGUGUACAGGCUAUGCAAUACCUUUGGUCACCAUCCUGAUCUGCAACCGGAAAGUCUACCAAGCUGUGCGGCACAAUAAAGCCACGGAAAACAAGGAAAAGAAGAGAAUCAUAAAACUACUUGUCAGCAUCACAGUUACUUUUGUCUUAUGCUUUACUCCCUUUCAUGUGAUGUUGCUGAUUCGCUGCAUUUUAGAGCAUGCUGUGAACUUCGAAGACCACAGCAAUUCUGGGAAGCGAACUUACACAAUGUAUAGAAUCACGGUUGCAUUAACAAGUUUAAAUUGUGUUGCUGAUCCAAUUCUGUACUGUUUUGUAACCGAAACAGGAAGAUAUGAUAUGUGGAAUAUAUUAAAAUUCUGCACUGGGAGGUGUAAUACAUCACAAAGACAAAGAAAACGCAUACUUUCUGUGUCUACAAAAGAUACUAUGGAAUUAGAGGUCCUUGAGUAGAACCAAGGAUGUUUUGAAGGGAAGGGAAGUUUAAGUUAUGCAUUAUUAUAUCAUCAAGAUUACAUUUUGAAAAGGAAAUCUAGCAUGUGAGGGGACUAAGUGUUCUCAGAGUGAUGUUUUAAUCCAGUCCAAUAAAAAUAUCUUAAAACUGCAUUGUACAGCUCCCUCCCUGCGUUUUAUUAAAUGAUGUAUAUUAAACAAAGAUCAAUAUUUUCUUAAUGACUCAGGGUCUUUAUUGUUAAUGCCAAUUGUUUUUGUAUCUGUGCUAUAAUCCCUUAGAGUCAGUAAAGUAUGUAGGGGACUGUUUCUUCCUUUGUGUCUGGGUUUAUGAUUUUUCUCACUCUUUCUUUGGACUCCAGGGUGUCAGCCAUCAGGUCUCCUAAUUUUGUGUACCGGUCUCCAACAACCCCAGCUACUGAAUACUGCUUCUAAUCUCCUCAUUCAUUAACAAAUCUUUAUUUUUUUAUCUUGUAUAAAAUAACUGCUUUAUUGACACAAAAUUUACAUAACUUAAAAUUCAACUUUGUAUUGUGUACAAUUCAGUGAUUUUUUGUAUAUUCACAGAGCUGUGCAACCAUCACCACACUCAAAAAAUUUUCAUCACCCACCAAAGAAAUCUUAUACUCUUAGCAGUCGCUCCCUGCUCUCCCGUCCAUGCCAGUUAUUAAUUUACUUUCUGUCUCUAAGGAUUUUCAUUACUCUGAACAUUUCAUAUAAAUAGAAUUAUACAAUAUGUGGCCUACUGUGACGUAUUUCACUUAGUAUAAUGGUUUCAAGUUUUAUCCAUGUGUAGAAUGUAUCAGCACUUCAUUUCUUUUUAUGGCCUGAUAGUAUUCUGUUGCAUGGUUAUACUCCAUUUUGUUUAUCUAAUCACUUGGCUUCAUUAACAAAUAUUUAUUGAAUCCAUUCCAUAAACUAGGUUUUGAGUUAAGUACUGGGGCUAUGAAAGAAAUGGUCUCAUGAAGCCUCACGAAGUUUACAUUAGUUCAAAAGCCUAGUCACCGAGCUUGAAAGAUUUCUAUAUAAAGGAAAAGGAAAUAGGCUCUGAGUUUUAUUUUGAUCUCUUUUUAAUUUAUAACUGGGUAUAACAUAGCUGAAAUUACCAGAAGUUUAAUGCAUAGACAAAUAAAUAGUUCUAUUAUAUCUUUCUUUUUGGACUUAGAAUGUUAGAAUAUUUUGAGAGUUCUUUUUUUUUUUUUUUUUGAGUCAGAGUCUUGCUCUGUAAUCCAGGCUAGAGUGUAGUGGUGCGAUCUCCACUCACUGCAGCCUCCACCUCCCAGGUUCAAGCGAUUCUCCUGCCUCAGCCUCCCAAGUAGCUGGGAUUACAGGCACCCACCACCAUGCCCAGCUAAUUUUUGUAUUUUUAGUAGAGACGGGGUUUCACCAUGUUGCACAGGCUGGUCUCAAUCGAACUCCUGACCUCAAGUGAUCAUCCCACCUAGGUCUCCCAAAGUGCUGAGAUGACAGGCGUGAGCCACCAUGCCUGGCAAAGAGAGUCUUGAUACAACAUAUUCUUUUGAAUCCUCAUUGUGUAAAUUGCCUCGUUGUAAAUAGACACUCAGUAAACAUUUUCCUCACCAAAAUAUUUUUAAGGAUUUUUCUACCCUUCUCCUUUUCUCUUUGCUUUCCUUUUCUUGCCUGUUCUUUCCACUCCCCCCAAAAUGAUCAGAUAGCAAAUGUCUUGAUAACAUGAGGUGCCCUCACAUUAAAAAACAAAAUAUUGAGCCGGGCGCGGUGGCUCAUGCCUGUAAUCCCAGCACUUUGGGAGGCUGAGGUGGGCAGAUCGCCUUAGGUCAGGAGUUGGAGACCAGGCUGACCAAUAUGAUGAAACUCUGUCUCUACUAAAAAUUCAAAAAUGUGCCAGACCUGGCCUGGUGGCAUGUGCCUGUAAUCCCAGCUACUUGGGAGGCUGAGUCAUAAGCCUGCAAUGGGAAAAUGGAUCGAAUCUGGGGUGAGGGGGAAGUGAUGUGGGGGUUAUGGUACCUCUUUUCUCUUCCAAAGAUGCUGUUCUUACUGCAUCACUUGUGGCUGGCCAGGAAAAGCCAUGCAGGAGUUUUGUUUGUGGCCACUAGGUGACGAUCGUGUUCUGUACGGGACCUCUUAUUAAUAGUUCACCACUAGCCGCCACUCCAGAAGAGCGGAGGAACCCAGGAUAAUAUUUUGUCAACCAAGAAACAAGAAGUCCCUCCCAGGAACUGGAAAUGAAUGGGGAAAAUGCUGAAAUCUCAUUUGCACUAUUCAUUUCUCUUCUCUCUGGAAAGCUCGGCAAUCAUCAGGUCAUUUCAUUUGGCUUAAAUUCCAUGUGUCUUUCCAAACUUUUAAAAGCUGGUGAAAAUUGUUCCACCCAUAUGUAAAAGAACAUAGGUUAAGUUGUCUAAUUCUUGCAGGAAUGUGGAUAUAGCAUUAAAAAUAUGUCUUUGUAUACUUAUCUUACCCAUGUAAGAAAAGAGUGGCCAACUUUCAUAUAAAUAGAAAGAGAACAUUUAAGCUAUAUGCAGUUUGCAUUUUUGUCUACUAUUAUGAAAUUAUUAUCUAUGAAAUUCAAGCUGUAACUCAACAUAUGUAUAAUUUUAAUUUCUAAUUUAUUGUUAGAUCUCAGCACUUAAAAAAUUACAUCUUGUAUUUGAAUUGUUAAAUCUGUUCCCUGCAAAGAACAGUAAUACAAUCAUGUUCUAAUUUACUAGCAUUUGCAUAUUUUAGAAAUAUAAUGGCCUGUAAUUUACUUUUCUUUUGCCUAUAAUUUUCUGAAGCUCUUUAUGAUGCACCGGUGCAUUUUUAUUUAAAAAAUAGAUUGUGACUCCUCAAAUAAUGUUACAAUUCGAUGUUCAAAAAGCAAUCCAGGUACAUAGCCAUAAAGGGAUGAGCUAGAGAGGUCUCCAUAUUAUCAUUCAAUGUGAGAAUAAAAAUUCUAUAUUUUAUUCUAGAAUAAAAUUAUAAAUUUCUUUAUCUA